AGAUAGAUCUUACAGGUCCCAGCCUGUAGACAUCUUUUACUCCAAUUUCCUGAAUAGAUAGCUUUAUUCCUUCAAGGUAAUAUAGUGCGGUGGCUUCUGGCUGAGAUGUUUGCUGUUGUUUUCUUCAUCUUGUCUUUGAUGACUUGUCAGCCUGGGGUAACUGCACAGGAGAAGGUGAACCAGAGAGUAAGACGGGCAGCUACACCCGCAGCAGUUACCUGCCAGCUGAGCAACUGGUCAGAGUGGACAGAUUGCUUUCCGUGCCAGGACAAAAAGUACCGACACCGGAGCCUCUUGCAGCCAAACAAGUUUGGGGGAACCAUCUGCAGUGGUGACAUCUGGGAUCAAGCCAGCUGCUCCAGUUCUACAACUUGUGUAAGGCAAGCACAGUGUGGACAGGAUUUCCAGUGUAAGGAGACAGGUCGCUGCCUGAAACGCCACCUUGUGUGUAAUGGAGACCAGGACUGCCUUGAUGGCUCUGAUGAGGACGACUGUGAAGAUGUCAGGGCCAUUGACGAAGACUGCAGCCAGUAUGAACCAAUUCCAGGAUCACAGAAGGCAGCCUUGGGGUACAAUAUCCUGACCCAGGAAGAUGCUCAGAGUGUGUACGAUGCCAGUUAUUAUGGGGGCCAGUGUGAGACGGUAUACAAUGGGGAAUGGAGGGAGCUUCGAUAUGACUCCACCUGUGAACGUCUCUACUAUGGAGAUGAUGAGAAAUACUUUCGGAAACCCUACAACUUUCUGAAGUACCACUUUGAAGCCCUGGCAGAUACUGGAAUCUCCUCAGAGUUUUAUGAUAAUGCAAAUGACCUUCUUUCCAAAGUUAAAAAAGACAAGUCUGACUCAUUUGGAGUGACCAUCGGCAUAGGCCCAGCCGGCAGCCCUUUAUUGGUGGGUGUAGGUGUAUCCCACUCACAAGACACUUCAUUCUUGAACGAAUUAAACAAGUAUAAUGAGAAGAAAUUCAUUUUCACAAGAAUCUUCACAAAGGUGCAGACUGCACAUUUUAAGAUGAGGAAGGAUGACAUUAUGCUGGAUGAAGGAAUGCUGCAGUCAUUAAUGGAGCUUCCAGAUCAGUACAAUUAUGGCAUGUAUGCCAAGUUCAUCAAUGACUAUGGCACCCAUUACAUCACAUCUGGAUCCAUGGGUGGCAUUUAUGAAUAUAUCCUGGUGAUUGACAAAGCAAAAAUGGAAUCCCUUGUUAUCAACUCUGGAAUGUUAACUGUUCUCUCAUCUGUAAAGUGGGGAUAAGAGGAAGAUCCAUCUCCCAGAGUUCUGCAAACACCCAGCUCUGAAACAUUGCUCAACUGGGAGGGAAAUCAUUAUCAUGAUGUCCAGCCUGCAGUGUCUGGUAUAUUUGCUGUGGACUUGGAGCCUCAGCAAUCAUGCCUCCUCCUCCACCUGCCCAUUUCUUUGAUCAAGGUCAUUCAUUUCUGUCUCCAGAGCUUCAUCCAGUUUUGGAGGGACCACUCUUCCCAUUUAUCAAGGUCACUUUGAACUCUCAUCACUAUCUUUCAAAGUGUUAACAACUCUGCUCAAAUCAGUGUGUGCUUUCCAUCAUCCCUGGCCCUGAUGGAUACCAGAUAACAGUGACCCUGGGAAAGACCCUUCCAGCAAGAGUUCAGUACAUCCAACCUAUUAUUGAUCAUCUUAUUCCAGUCAGGGCUUGUGGACCAGCCAGUCUACCACCUAACACACAAUGUCUAAAAAGCUACAGGGACAGAAGUUAAAACCUCACCAAAGUUAAUGCCAAUUAUAGCUCUACAUCCUCUUCCUCCUCCCUCCCUGCCUUCCUGUAUUUCAUUCAGUCCUCUAGCCUUUCCCUCGACAAACAUUUAUGAAGUACACAUAACAUGGGAAACACUGUCUAGAUACCAAGAUGCUUAAUACAUUGUCCCUCUCAUCAGGGGGCUCAUAGAAAGUAAGGGGGUUUCUCUUUGUCAUAAUCAUCAGAUUAUGGUCAGGGAUAAUUUACUCUGUGGACAGCCAAAUUGGUUACCACCCAAAGUGAACUAGCAAUUUAUUUUCUUAUUCACUAUUUUGUUUUAAUACAAUGUUUUUGCGUAUAAUAACAUCUACUAUUUGUAGAGCAUAACACAUCUGGCAUUCAAAUUGAUCCUCAUAAUAACUUUAUGAGGAAUUAUAUUGUUAUUUUCCCCAGUUUUAUAGAAAGAAAGUUGAAAUCCAAAGAGGUUAAGUAAAUGGCUCAGUGUGACUCACUUAGUAUUGAACCUAGGUCUUCUGAUUUAGAUUUUGUAUAUCUUCCAAGUACUCAUCCCUUUUUCCAUACAUUCUGUCAUUCAUUCUGAUACUAUAUGUGAGAGGCUUAGACUUUAGCAGUGGUGGUAAGUCAGCCAAGAUUUACUGAGUAUUCACUGUGUGGUAGACAUUAGGGUAAACACCUUAAAUGCACCAUCUCAUUUAAUUCUCAGGAGAGACUUGUGAAGAGGAUACUAUUAUAUAAUCUCCAAUUCACAAAAGAAGAACUGAGACUCAGUGAUUUUCUGUUAAAUAGCUUGCCCAAGGUCACAUAGCUAUUACUUGGUGAAGUCAAACUCAAGAACCUGUAAUGUUAAGCAAGGUGCUAUAAUGUCUCAAGGAUGCCUUAACCUAGGAUUUUUCAAACUUCAGACCAUAACCCAUUAGUAGAUUGUAAAAGAAAUUCAGUGGGUCAUGAUCAGCAUUUAAAAAAUAAAAUGUAAUAGAACACAAAGUAUCAAAGUAUGUCACACAAAGUGUAGUUAAGUAUUUAAACUUUUAAGCCAAGCACAGUGGCUCCUUCUUGUAAUCCUAGCAUUUUUGGAGGCCAAGUCUGGAGGAUCAUUUGAGCCCAGGAGUUUGAGACCAGCCUGGGCAACAUAGGGAGACCAUAUCUCUAUAAAAAUUAAACAAACAAACAAAAAACUAGCCAGGCAUGGUACAUGUGCCUGUAGUCCCGGCUACUUGGGAGGAUGAGGUGGGAGGAUCACUUGAGCCUGGGAGGUCGAGGUUGCAGUGAGCCAAGAUCACACCAUUGCACUGCAGCCUGGAUAACAGAGAGAGGCCCUGUCUCAAAAAGAAAAGAAACUUCUUUUAAAUGAAUGUGUGUAGACUGAUCAUGAUGUAAAAUGUAUUUCUUACUUUGAGAGUGGUCAAGAAAGUAUUGAAAACACAGUCUUAACUCAGUGUGCUCUACUAACUAUAAAAACAUAUUUAAUUACUUUAAAUAAAGGAAAAAUCAUCAAUAGCCCUAA